GUAUCGCUCCUCGUAGGCCGGGGCUCGGCGCGCGCACCCGCACUAAAGACGCUUCUUCCCGGCGGGUAGGAAUCCCGCCGGCGAGCCGAACAGUUCCCCGAGCGCAGCCCGCGGACCACCACCCGGCCGCACGGGCCGCUUUUGUCCCCCGCCCGCCGCUUCUGUCCGAGAGGCCGCCCGCGAGGCGCAUCCUGACCGCGAGCGUCGGGUCCCAGAGCCGGGCGCGGCUGGGGCCCGAGGCUAGCAUCUCUCGGGAGCCGCAAGGCGAGAGCUGCAAAGUUUAAUUAGACACUUCAGAAUUUUGAUCACCUAAUGUUGAUUUCAGAUGUAAAAGUCAAGAGAAGACUCUAAAAAUAGCAAAGAUGCUUUUGAGCCAGAAUGCCUUCAUCUUCAGAUCACUUAAUUUGGUUCUCAUGGUGUAUAUCAGCCUCGUGUUUGGUAUUUCAUAUGAUUCGCCUGAUUACACAGAUGAAUCUUGCACUUUCAAGAUAUCAUUGCGAAAUUUCCGGUCCAUCUUAUCAUGGGAAUUAAAAAACCACUCCAUUGUACCAACUCACUAUACAUUGCUGUAUACAAUCAUGAGUAAACCAGAAGAUUUGAAGGUGGUUAAGAACUGUGCAAAUACCACAAGAUCAUUUUGUGACCUCACAGAUGAGUGGAGAAGCACACACGAGGCCUAUGUCACCGUCCUAGAAGGAUUCAGCGGGAACACAACGUUGUUCAGUUGCUCACACAAUUUCUGGCUGGCCAUAGACAUGUCUUUUGAACCACCAGAGUUUGAGAUUGUUGGUUUUACCAACCACAUUAAUGUGAUGGUGAAAUUUCCAUCUAUUGUUGAGGAAGAAUUACAGUUUGAUUUAUCUCUCGUCAUUGAAGAACAGUCAGAGGGAAUUGUUAAGAAGCAUAAACCCGAAAUAAAAGGAAACAUGAGUGGAAAUUUCACCUAUAUCAUUGACAAGUUAAUUCCAAACACGAACUACUGUGUAUCUGUUUAUUUAGAGCACAGUGAUGAGCAAGCAGUAAUAAAGUCUCCCUUAAAAUGCACCCUCCUUCCACCUGGCCAGGAAUCAGAAUCAGCAGAAUCUGCCAAAAUAGGAGGAAUAAUUACUGUGUUUUUGAUAGCAUUGGUCUUGACAAGCACCAUAGUGACACUGAAAUGGAUUGGUUAUAUAUGCUUAAGAAAUAGCCUCCCCAAAGUCUUGAGGCAAGGUCUCGCUAAGGGCUGGAAUGCAGUGGCUAUUCACAGGUGCAGUCAUAAUGCACUACAGUCUGAAACUCCUGAGCUCAAACAGUCGUCCUGCCUAAGCUUCCCCAGUAGCUGGGAUUACAAGCGUGCAUCCCUGUGCCCCAGUGAUUAAGUUUUAUUAUGUAGAAAAUAAAGAGCAAACAGUACAGCUGAUACGGACUCUCUCUCUCUUUUUUUUUUUUUUUAAGAAUUUUCAUAACUUUUUAGCCUGGCCAUUUCCUAACCUGCCACCGUUGGAAGCCAUGGAUAUGGUGGAGGUCAUUUACAUCAACAGAAAGAAGAAAGUGUGGGAUUAUAAUUAUGAUGAUGAAAGUGAUAGCGAUACUGAGGCAGCGCCCAGGACAAGUGGCGGUGGCUAUACCAUGCAUGGACUGACUGUCAGGCCUCUGGGUCAGGCCUCUGCCACCUCUACAGAAUCCCAGUUGAUAGACCCGGAGUCCGAGGAGGAGCCUGACCUGCCUGAGGUUGAUGUGGAGCUCCCCACGAUGCCAAAGGACAGCCCUCAGCAGUUGGAACUCUUGAGUGGGCCCUGUGAGAGGAGAAAGAGUCCACUCCAGGACCCUUUUCCCGAAGAGGACUACAGCUCCACGGAGGGGUCUGGGGGCAGAAUUACCUUCAAUGUGGACUUAAACUCUGUGUUUUUGAGAGUUCUUGAUGACGAGGACAGUGACGACUUAGAAGCCCCUCUGAUGCUAUCGUCUCAUCUGGAAGAGAUGGUUGACCCAGAGGAUCCUGAUAAUGUGCAAUCAAACCAUUUGCUGGCCAGCGGGGAAGGGACACAGCCAACCUUUCCCAGCCCCUCUUCAGAGGGCCUGUGGUCCGAAGAUGCUCCAUCUGAUCAAAGUGACACUUCUGAGUCAGAUGUUGACCUUGGGGAUGGUUAUAUAAUGAGAUGACUCCAAAACUAUUGAAUGAACUUGGACAGACAAGCACCUACAGGGUUCUUUGUCUCUGCAUCCUAACUUGCUGCCUUAUCGUCUGCAAGUGUUCUCCAAGGGAAGGAGGAGGAAACUGUGGUGUUCCUUUCUUCCAGGUGACAUCACCUAUGCACAUUCCCAGUAUGGGGACCAUAGUAUCAUUCAGUGCAUUGUUUACAUAUUCAAAGUGGUGCACUUUGAAGGAAGCACAUGUGCACCUUUCCUUUACACUAAUGCACUUAGGAUGUUUCUGCAUCAUGUCUACCAGGGAGCAGGGUUCCCCACAGUUUCAGAGGUGGUCCAGGACCCUAUGAUAUUUCUCUUCUUUCGUUCUUUUUUUUUUUUUUUUUUGAGACAGAGUCUCGUUCUGUCGCCCAAGCUGGAGCGCAAUGGUGUGAUCUUGGCUCACUGCAACAUCCGCCUCCCAGGUUCAAGUGAUUCUCCUGCCUCAGCCUCCCUCGCAAGUAGCUGGGAUUACAGGCGCCUGCCACCAUGCCUAGCAAAUUUUUGUAUUUUUAGUAGAGACAGGAUUUUACCAUGUUGGCCAGGCUGGUCUCAAACUCCUGACCUCAAGUGAUCUGCCCUCCUCAGCCUCGUAAAGUGCUGGGAUUACAGGGGUGAGCCGCUGUGCCUGGCUGGCCCUGUGAUAUUUCUGUGAAAUAAAUUGGGCCAGGGUGGGAGCAGGGAAAGAAAAGGAAAAUAGUAGCAAGAGCUGCAAAGCAGGCAGGAAGGGAGGAGGAGAGCCAGGUGAGCAGUGGAGAGAAGGGGGGCCCUGCACAAGGAAACAGGGAAGAGCCAUCGAAGUUUCAGUCGGUGAGCCUUGGGCACCUCACCCAUGUCACAUCCUGUCUCCUGCAAUUGGAAUUCCACCUUGUCCAGCCCUCCCCAGUUAAAGUGGGGAAGACAGACUUUAGGAUCACGUGUGUGACUAAUACAGAAAGGAAACAUGGCGUCGGGGAGAGGGAUAAAACCUGAAUGCCAUAUUUUAAGUUAAAAAAAAAAAAAGCAAACACAAAGAUGCUUCAAGAUCUUCAGGAGAAGUAUGGUAUACAAGUUUCAGGGACCCUAUUUGACAAUUUUCAGAGUGCUCUCUAUGCUGAUUCCGAGUCGAGUGUGUCAGCUGUGAUUACAGUGCCUGUGGAUCUAGGCCGGGUUGGGGGGGUGUGGGCGGGGGAAGGGAAGUCUGGCCCGGAGCAAUUGCUCCUGCCGGUAACCCCAGCACUUUGGGAUGCCUAAACAGGCGUAUCGCUUGAGGCCAGUAAUUCGAGACCAGCCUGGGCAACAUGGCAAAUCUGUCUCUACAAAACAAAAUUAGAAAAAUUAACUGGGCGUAGUGGCAUGUGCCUGUUGUCCCAGCUACUUGGGAGGCUGAGGUGGGAGAAUGGCUUGAGCCCAGGAAGCGGAGGUUGCAGUGAGCCAAGAUCAUGUCACUGCACUUCAGCCUGGGUGACAGAACCAGACCCUGUCUUUAAAAAGGGAGUUGGUGGGGAGAGGUUCUAGAAUGUCAUGUAGCAACCAGUUUAAGGACUGGGACUCAGGGAUCCAACUCCCACAGUUUCCCUGUGUGACCCUAGGCAUUUGACUUAGCCUUUCUGAGCCUCAGGUUUUUUGUUUCUGAAGUAAAAGGAUUGGACUAGGUAAUCUCCAAGAUCCUAGGAACCCAGGAGAAAGAUGAGAAAAUGUACAAGAAUGAACACUCAGGUGGAAAUGCUGCAAUCCUGAGAAGCUCCCAGGAUGAAUGAAAGGCACAGGACCUCUUACCCCUCACCCCUGCCCCCCUCAAGAGCUGGUUUCUCAAACCUUUCUCUUAGGCCCCUUCAAAGGGGGAAAACUAAAAAUUAUACAAGUUAUAGUUCAAGGACUUUAAAUAGAUUAUUUAUAUGAUUGCUCAUAAGGAUGAGGCUGUGAGGAGGGAACACCUUAUUUAAUCUAAUGAAAUUCCAUAGGAAAGAGGCCUUUUGUAUAUUGAAUCAAUUUAUCUGCCUUCUCAGUGCAUCUGUCAUAUUCUGAAAGAUUCUGGGUUGAUCUUUUGCGAUAACCUCUAUGGCUGUGAGUGUGUGUGUGUGUUUGUGUAUUUUUUAACAUUUUGUAUAAUGAUUGGAGGUUGGUAAAAAGUAACACAACAGUACUUUUUUAAUACAAA